GCGCACAGGGCCCGCGCCAGCGACCAUGGCGGAGCCCACAGUGUGCUCCUUCCUCACCAAGGUGCUGUGCGCCCACGGCGGCCGCAUGUUCCUGAAGGACCUGCGCGGCCACGUGGAGCUGUCGGAGGCCAGGCUCCGGGACGUGCUGCAGCGCGCCGGGCCCGAGCGUUUCCUGCUGCAGGAGGUGGAGACGCAGGAGGGCCUCGGGGACGCGGAGGCCGAGGCGGCGGCCGGCGCGGUGGGCGGUGGCGGCACCUCCGCCUGGAGGGUGGUGGCCGUGUCCUCUGUGCGCCUCUGCGCCCGCUACCAGCGCGGCGAGUGCCAGGCCUGCGACCAGCUGCACUUCUGCCGCCGGCACAUGCUGGGCAAGUGCCCCAACCGGGACUGCUGGUCUACCUGUACCCUUUCCCAUGAUAUCCACACACCUGUCAACAUGCAGGUCCUGAAAAGCCAUGGACUUUUUGGUCUCAAUGAAAACCAGCUUCGGAUCCUGCUUUUGCAGAAUGACCCCUGUCUUUUACCAGAGGUCUGUUUGCUCUACAACAAAGGGGAAGCCCUGUAUGGCUACUGCAACCUCAAGGAUAAAUGCAACAAGUUUCAUGUGUGCAAAUCCUUUGUGAAAGGAGAAUGCAAACUUCAGACCUGCAAACGGUCCCAUCAGCUUAUCCAUGCUGCAUCUUUGAAGCUGCUACAGGACCAAGGACUGAAUAUUCCAAGUGUUGUUAAUUUUCAGAUAAUCUCCACCUACAAGCAUAUGAAGCUGCACAAGAUGCUUGAAAAUACAGAUAAUUCAUCACCUUCGACUGAGCAUUCACAAGGCCUUGAGAAGCAAGGAGUGCACGCAGCUGGAGCUGCAGAAGCUGGUCCUCUGGCUUCUGUCCCUGCUCAGUCGGCCAAGAAGCCCUGCCCAGAUGGAGUCUCUGUCGCCCAGGCUGGAGUACAGUGGCAUGAUCUCAGCUCACUGCAACCUCCGUCUCCCAGGUUCAAGUGAUUCUCCUGCCUCAGCCUCCCGAGUAGCUGGGAUUAUAGGCAUGUACCACCAUGCCUGGCUAAUUUUUGUAUUUUUAGUAGAGAUGGGGUUUCACCAUGUUGGCCAGGCUGGUCUUGAACUCCUCACCUCAAGUGAUCCACCCACCUCGCCCUCCCAAAGUGUUAGUAUUAUAGGCGUGAGCCACUGCACUCAGCCUGAUGUUCCCUCUUUUAUAAGUGCCAUUCCUUCUUCCUACCUCACAACCUAGCAAAAUUGGAUUCUUCAAAACGCCAGGUUGGCCUUUCUUGACUCCAAAAGAGGUGACUCUUGUAGCAUUCUUACAGGCCUAACAUAGCACUUACUUUAUGUUGCAAUGCUGUGUGCAAUGCUGUGUUUUUUUACUCACUAGCUCUGAGCAAAACAUUAUUUAUUCUUGGUAAUUGUAACACUUGGUAGUGAAGACAUAUUUUUUGCCAUAUAAUGGAUUAUACUUUGUAUUUGAAUCCAUGUGAAUCAGUAGCAUAUUGGUCUUCAUUGUUUUUCCUCCUUCUCCGACGUUUUUUUGAGACAGGGUCUCACUCUGUUGCCCAGGCUGGAGUGCAGGGCACAAUUACAGCUCCCUGCAGCCUUGAUUUCUCAGGCUCAAGCCAUCCUCUUGCCUCAGCUUCCCUAGUAGCCGGGACUAUAGGUGCAUGCCACCAUACUCAGCUAAUCUUUUUAGGUUUUUAGUAGAGACAAGGUCUCACUAUGUUGCCCAGGCUGGUCUUGAACUCCUAAGCUCAAGCAGUCCUCCCGCCUUGGCCUCUGAAUGUGCUGGGAUUACAGGCAUGAGCCACUAUGCCUAACCAUAUUUUUUCCAAUAUUAAAAAAUCUUUUUUUCCCCCUAAGGAAUGUGUUAUAUAAGGUCAACAUGUUUUUAGUGCUUCAGUUUGACUUGUCUACAUCUAAAGUUAACUCUUUAAGGCUUACAUUUAUGAUUAUAAUUCUUUCCAUCGAGGGAUUUAGUCUCCAUUAUUGUCAUGUUUCUUGAUUUUUUUCAUUAUACUUGGUUCUUCUUUUUGUCUAGGUUUUAUAUAUACCUUAAUUAAUUCUUUCUUGGCUGUUUUAUAUCUAUGUUGCUGUCAGCAUGGGAAUCUCUAUUAUUAGAAAGCUAUUAACUUUUAAAAUAUGUAUCUUUUGGUGAUUUUCUUUGUUCUAACAGUUUUAGAUGGCCUGUUUGCUCUUUCUAAAUAUAAAAUCAUAGGUAUUUCUAUUUUGUUUUUGUGUUUCAUAAAAUUGUAAUAAGUUUUUUUGAUAUUUUUUCAUUACAUAUGAAGUUAAUUGUUGGUUUUAAACAAAUGUUCUUUGUUAGGAUAACAGAAAUAACAUCUUCUAUUCUUGUUUGUUGGAAGCUAAAAGCUUGAUAAAAGGAAUUGGUGUCUUUUGAUACAAUCAAAUUUUUAUCACUUAAAUUGCCUAAUAUGAUUAUAAUAAGGGUUUUUGUAAUAUUAAAACAUCCUUAAAUUCCUGAGAUAAAACUCUACCUGGUUAUAGUAUAUGUUCUUUUAAUGUAUUAUCUUUCCUAUUUGCUGUACAUCUAUACAUUCAUAAAUAAAAUUCAUUUAUAUUUUA